AUGCUGGGGCCGCGCCGCUACUCCCUCCGCACGGCCCCACGCUUUUCGCCCUGAAGGAAUCGGUACGAGACGGCUCACCUAGGCAGCCCGCAGCCCGUGGUAGUGCCGGAGCCUUGCUCCUCUUCACUCAUUCCCUCCUCCGUCCCCGCGGGCGCCACCGUGACUGCAGCCUCCACGCGCCCCAAUACACAGCCGACGAGCUAGGGCCGGGGCCAAGCCCGGAGUCGCGGCCGGUAGGGCCCGCCGCGGGGCACGCUGGGAUAUGGAGUCCCCCGCCCACCCUACUUCGUGAGCCUCCAUCUGGAGGGGAGCUAUCCGCCCCACAACCCUCUGCGUGCGUGGCUCGCCCGGGCAGGCUGCACCGCCUUCUGGGAGGAGCGGGCCCUCCGCCGUCGCUUCUCGAGAAGGCCGUAUUUUUUUGUUUGUAAUACCGUCCCGCCUCCUUCCUUCCGCGCCCCCUCUCUCCCGGUCCGUGAAGCUGUGGACAUGCGUACUAGCGGAGGGGAAGCCGCUGGGUAGGGAGGCGGUAAGGACUCACUUGGGCACGGAGCCUUUUGGAUCGCGAGAAAACUACAGAACCCAAGAGCCCGCGCGCCAUCUGUGUCGCAGCUGGAGAGGCAGGGUCAAGCACGCACGAGAAGCUUCAUGGCGUCAUUGGUUACUCCCAUUGCGAUUACUUCCCCUAGGUGCACUGAGAUUGGUUACUUCGACUAAAGGGGCGGAGACAAGGAAAAGUCAGCCCCCCCCGACCCCGCCUCCUUGAUGAAGGAAGGUUGUGAUUGGUCCGGAGAGGCUGCCGUCGGAUCCUGGCUCUUUGCGGUCUGGGAGGGUGGGCCUUACCUAGACGCCGGAGGGGACCGAUCUCUGUUUCCGCAGGGCUCUGGAGCUGGUGCAGGUUUAAGUCCGUCUCAGACAGUCCCCUCAACCCACAGCCUAAGCCCCUUGCCCUUGGGCCUCCGUGACACAGAACUUGCUUCCUUUUCCUAGGUCGUCCUUCACCUCCCUUCAGGUGUUGCUUCUUUUGUGAAACCUUUUUAGAACCGCUCUAGUGAACCUCUCUUUAACUGGCGAGGAAACCUCUGGGGCCUGAUAAUCAGGCUGUAAUGUGGGACGACAGGAUUAGAAGGACUAGGCACCUUGGUGGUCUUGUUCCCUCUUCCAUGAGUCUUGGGUCUCUCAGCUGAAGAGAGCAAAAGUGAAUUUUGGCCGCCUAAGAUUAAUCAACUGAUCUGGGUGUUGAGCAGACGCGCAUUGUUUAGUCCUAGAGCCCCAUUGCCUCCUCCCCCAAAGUUGCACAACCACUGGGCUGAGGGAAAUCUUGUGACCUUGGAGAGAGAAAGGGAGAGACCACAUUAAAAAAAAAAAAGGUUCUAAUGAGUGUUCUGAGAAGGGGUCAAGAAAGAUGUCUUACUCUGAGCCGGGGUUGGAGGUCCAGAGGAAUCUUGAAAUGAUAAUGAGGGGUCAUCCAGGAACACUGGAGGAGGAUGGGGCCUAGAGCCGAGUGAAUUCCAAGGCCCAGUGUUCACCAUCAUACCAGGGGCCAGAGGCGAUGGCUUGCCUCCAUGAGACCCGAACACCCUCUCCUUCCUUUGGGGGCUUUGUGUCUACCCUAAGUGAGGCAUCCAUGCGCAAGCUGGACCCAGACACUUCUGACUGCACUCCCGAGAAGGACCUGACGCCUACCCAGUGUGUACUUCGAGAUGUGGUACCCCUUGGUGGGCAGGGUGGGGGAGGGCCCAGCCCCUCCCCAGGUGGAGAGCCGCCCCCUGAGCCUUUUGCCAACAGUGUCCUGCAGCUACAUGAGCAGGAUGCAGGGGGCCCAGGGGGAGCAGCUGGGUCACCUGAGAGUCGGGCAUCCAGAGUUCGAGCUGACGAGGUGCGACUGCAGUGCCAGAGUGGCAGUGGCUUCCUUGAGGGCCUCUUUGGCUGCCUGCGCCCUGUCUGGACCAUGAUUGGCAAAGCCUACUCCACUGAGCACAAGCAGCAGCAGGAAGACCUUUGGGAGGUCCCCUUUGAGGAAAUCCUGGACCUGCAGUGGGUGGGCUCAGGGGCCCAGGGUGCUGUCUUCCUGGGGCGCUUCCACGGGGAGGAGGUGGCUGUGAAGAAGGUGCGAGACCUCAAAGAAACCGACAUCAAGCACUUGCGAAAGCUGAAGCACCCCAACAUCAUCACUUUCAAGGGUGUGUGCACCCAGGCUCCCUGCUACUGCAUCCUCAUGGAGUUCUGCGCCCAGGGCCAGCUGUAUGAGGUACUGCGGGCUGGCCGCCCUGUCACCCCCUCCUUACUGGUUGACUGGUCCAUGGGCAUCGCUGGUGGCAUGAACUACCUGCACCUGCACAAGAUUAUCCACAGGGAUCUCAAGUCACCCAACAUGCUAAUCACCUACGACGAUGUGGUGAAGAUCUCAGAUUUUGGCACUUCCAAGGAGCUGAGUGACAAGAGCACCAAGAUGUCCUUUGCAGGGACAGUAGCCUGGAUGGCCCCUGAGGUGAUCCGCAAUGAACCUGUGUCUGAGAAGGUCGACAUCUGGUCCUUUGGCGUGGUGCUAUGGGAACUGCUGACUGGUGAGAUCCCCUACAAAGACGUAGAUUCCUCAGCCAUUAUCUGGGGUGUGGGAAGCAACAGUCUCCAUCUGCCCGUGCCCUCCAGUUGCCCAGAUGGUUUCAAGAUCCUGCUUCGCCAGUGCUGGAAUAGCAAACCACGAAAUCGCCCAUCAUUCCGACAGAUCCUGCUGCAUCUGGACAUUGCCUCAGCUGAUGUACUCUCCACACCCCAGGAGACUUACUUUAAGUCCCAGGCAGAGUGGCGGGAAGAAGUAAAACUGCACUUUGAAAAGAUUAAGUCAGAAGGGACCUGUCUGCACCGCCUAGAAGAGGAACUGGUGAUGAGGAGGAGGGAGGAGCUCAGACACGCCCUGGACAUCAGGGAGCACUAUGAAAGGAAGCUGGAGAGAGCCAACAACCUGUAUAUGGAACUUAAUGCCCUCAUGUUGCAGCUGGAACUCAAGGAGAGGGAGCUGCUCAGGCGAGAGCAAGCUUUAGAGCGGAGGUGCCCAGGCCUGCUGAAGCCACACCCUUCCCGGGGCCUCCUGCAUGGAAACACAAUGGAGAAGCUUAUCAAGAAGAGGAAUGUGCCACAGAAGCUGUCACCCCAUAGCAAAAGGCCAGAUAUCCUCAAGACGGAGUCUUUGCUCCCUAAACUAGAUGCAGCCCUGAGUGGGGUGGGGCUUCCUGGGUGUCCUAAGGGCCCCCCCUCACCAGGACGGAGUCGCCGUGGCAAGACCCGUCACCGCAAGGCCAGCGCCAAGGGGAGCUGUGGGGACCUGCCUGGGCUUCGUACAGCUGUGCCACCCCAUGAACCUGGAGGACCAGGAAGCCCAGGGGGCCUAGGAGGGGGACCCUCAGCCUGGGAGGCCUGCCCUCCCGCCCUCCGUGGGCUUCAUCAUGACCUCCUGCUCCGCAAAAUGUCUUCAUCGUCCCCAGACCUGCUGUCAGCAGCACUAGGGUCCCGGGGCCGGGGGGCCACAGGCGGAGCUGGGGAUCCUGGCUCACCACCUCCGGCCCGGGGUGACACCCCACCAAGUGAGGGCUCAGCCCCUGGCUCCACCAGCCCAGAUUCACCUGGGGGAGCCAAAGGGGAACCACCUCCUCCAGUAGGGCCUGGUGAAGGUGUGGGGCUUCUGGGAACUGGAAGGGAAGGGACCUCAGGCCGGGGAGGAAGCCGGGCUGGGUCCCAGCACUUGACCCCAGCUGCACUGCUGUACAGGGCUGCCGUCACCCGAAGUCAGAAACGUGGCAUCUCAUCGGAAGAGGAGGAAGGAGAGGUAGACAGUGAAGUAGAGCUGACAUCAAGCCAGAGGUGGCCUCAGAGCCUGAACAUGCGCCAGUCACUAUCUACCUUCAGCUCAGAGAAUCCAUCAGAUGGGGAGGAAGGCACAGCUAGUGAACCUUCCCCCAGUGGCACACCUGAAGUUGGCAGCACCAACACUGAUGAGCGGCCAGAUGAGCGGUCUGAUGACAUGUGCUCCCAGGGCUCAGAAAUCCCACUGGACCCACCUCCUUCAGAGGUCAUCCCUGGCCCUGAACCCAGCUCCCUGCCCAUUCCACACCAGGAACUUCUCAGAGAGCGGGGCCCUCCCAAUUCUGAGGACUCAGACUGUGACAGCACUGAAUUGGACAACUCCAACAGCGUUGAUGCCUUGCGGCCCCCAGCUUCCCUCCCUCCAUGAAAGCCACUCGUAUUCCUUGUACAUAGAGAAAUAUUUAUAUAAAUUAUAUAUAUAUACAUAUAUAUAUAUAUAUGCGCCACAUAAUCAACAGAAAGAUGGGGCUGUCCCAGCCGUAAGUCAGGCUCGAGGGAGACUGAUCCCCUGACCAAUUCACCUGAUAAACUCUAGGGACACUGGCAGCUGUGGAAAUGAAUGAGGCACAGCCGUAGAGCUGUGGCUAAGGGCAAGCCCCUUCCUGCCCCACCCCAUUCCUUAUAUUCAGCAAGCAACAAGGCAAUAGAAAAGCCAGGGUUGUCUUUAUAUUCUUUAUCCCCAAAUAAUAGGGGGUGGGGGGAGGGGCGGUGGGAGGGGCAGGAGAGAAAACCACUUAGACUGCACUUUUCUGUUCCGUUUACUCUGUUUACACAUUUUGCACUUGGGAGGAGGGAGGCUAAGGCUGGGUCCUCCCCUCUGAGGUUUCUCAGGUGGCAAUGUAACUCAUUUUUUUGUCCCACCAUUUAUCUUCUCUGCCCAAGCCCUGUCUUAAGGCCCAGGGGGAGGUUAGGAGACUGAUAGCAUGUGAUGGCUCAGGCUGAAGAACCGGGGUGCUGUUUAAGUCCCUGCUUUUAUCCUGGUGCCUGAUUGGGGUGGGGACUGUCCUACUGUAACCCCUGUGAAAAACCUUGAAAUAUAACACUCCAUGCAGGCCCAGCUGUUGAGGGUUUUCUUGAUGAAUGAAUGGGGUACCAUACAUGGUUAAGAUAAAGCCUUGGGCUCCGGACUUUAUCUGAGGUGUCUGGAGAAGUUCUCCUGCCCCUCCACUUUUUUGCAUCUACUCUCACUAAAUGAGUAUAAUGUCAAGCCCCAACUUUCUAAAAUUAUAGGAAUAAAUGGUAGCAGAUACAUCCUUCUAACUUGUUAUGGAGGACUAUAAAUGAAGUUACUAAAAACAAUAGACUGAAAUUUUUAGUUUAAAAUAUGCAAGCCUGAACAAGGGGACCAACAUUCCCAAGAAACUGGAACCCAGUCAGACAUAUGAUCAACUGCUUAAUGUGUAUGCCAUGUAUGUCAUGUGUCAUUCCUUUCCCCCACCCCCUCCCUAGUGGAAGUGCUUGCCUACUCCCCUAGGACAGGUAAGUCCUCGGAAAGUCUAAUCCUCAAUCUUUUGGGCACAAGUUUUAUAAGGGCCAACCAAGCAUGGAGUCAGGGAAAAAUAGGAUCGAGGGCCACAAAAAAAGAUGGAAGUGGUAAAAUAGAAGAAAACAUCUUAACCGGAAUAAAGGCUUCCAUUCAAAACCCAAGAAGGGUCCUUUGAGGGAUAAAAGGUACAAAAAUAACAGCAAGACAAGAGGAAUAAAACCCACAUGAAUCACUGUGGCAUCCAGUUUCUAUUCACAAAGAAAAAGCUCCAGUCCAUCUUUUAAUUUUUUUGAAAAAUUCCUGACAUUACAGAACUAAACUGAAAUGUAUUAAUAUUCCACUCUUACAUUUCCAUGACAAACAGAAAAAUUCAUGAGCCAAAAAAAAAAAACCA